AGAGCGUGGAGCGCUGCGCGGCGCGGCGGCCGGGCCCUCGAGACGGGGACGGACACACCAGCCCCUCGGAUACCACUUGGCCACUCCCGCUGAGGCCACUCCCACUGCGUGGCUGAAGCCUCGAGGUCACCAGGCGGAGGCGCGGAGAUGCCCCUGCAUCAGCUGGGGGACAAGCCGCUCACCUUCCCCAGCCCCAACUCAGCCAUGGAAAACGGGCUUGACCACACCCCACCCAGCAGGAGGGCAUCCCCGGGCACACCCCUGAGCCCCGGCUCCCUCCGCUCCGCUGCCCAUAGCCCCCUGGACACCAGCAAGCAGCCCCUCUGCCAGCUCUGGGCCGAGAAGCAUGGCGCCCGGGGGACCCAUGAGGUGCGGUACGUCUCGGCCGGGCAGAGCGUGGCGUGCGGCUGGUGGGCCUUCGCACCGCCGUGCCUGCAGGUCCUCAACACGCCCAAGGGCAUCCUGUUCUUCCUGUGUGCGGCCGCAUUCCUGCAGGGGAUGACUGUGAAUGGCUUCAUCAACACAGUCAUCACCUCCCUGGAGCGCCGCUAUGACCUGCACAGCUACCAGAGCGGGCUCAUCGCCAGCUCCUACGACAUUGCCGCCUGCCUCUGCCUCACCUUCGUCAGCUACUUCGGGGGCUCAGGGCACAAGCCGCGCUGGCUGGGCUGGGGCGUGCUGCUUAUGGGCACGGGGUCGCUGGUGUUCGCGCUGCCCCACUUCACGGCUGGCCGCUAUGAGGUGGAGUUGGACGCGGGUGUCAGGACGUGCCCUGCCAACCCCGGCGCGGUGUGUGCGGACAGCACCUCGGGCCUGUCCCGCUACCAGCUGGUCUUCAUGCUGGGCCAGUUCCUGCAUGGCGUGGGUGCCACACCCCUCUACACGCUGGGCGUCACCUACCUGGAUGAGAACGUCAAGUCCAGCUGCUCGCCCGUCUACAUUGCCAUCUUCUACACAGCGGCCAUCCUGGGCCCAGCUGCCGGCUACCUGAUUGGAGGUGCCCUGCUGAAUAUCUACACGGAAAUGGGCCGACGGACGGAGCUGACCACCGAGAGCCCACUGUGGGUCGGCGCCUGGUGGGUCGGCUUCCUGGGCUCUGGGGCCGCUGCUUUCUUCACCGCCGUUCCCAUCCUUGGUUACCCUCGGCAGCUGCCAGGCUCCCAGCGCUACGCGGUCAUGAGAGCGGCGGAAAUGCACCAGUUGAAGGACAGCAGCCGUGGGGAGGCGAGCAACCCGGACUUUGGGAAAACCAUCAGAGACCUGCCUCUCUCCAUCUGGCUCCUGCUGAAGAACCCCACGUUCAUCCUGCUCUGCCUGGCCGGGGCCACCGAGGCCACUCUCAUCACCGGCAUGUCCACGUUCAGCCCCAAGUUCUUGGAGUCCCAGUUCAGCCUGAGUGCCUCAGAAGCUGCCACCUUGUUUGGGUACCUGGUGGUGCCAGCGGGUGGUGGCGGCACCUUCCUGGGCGGCUUCUUUGUGAACAAGCUCAGGCUCCGGGGCUCCGCGGUCAUCAAGUUCUGCCUGUUCUGCACCGUUGUCAGCCUGCUGGGCAUCCUCGUCUUCUCACUGCACUGCCCCAGUGUGCCCAUGGCGGGCGUCACAGCCAGCUACGGCGGGAGCCUCCUGCCCGAAGGCCACCUGAACCUAACGGCUCCCUGCAACGCUGCCUGCAGCUGCCAGCCAGAACACUACAGCCCUGUGUGCGGCUCGGACGGCCUCAUGUACUUCUCACUGUGCCACGCAGGGUGCCCUGCAGCCACGGAGACGAAUGUGGACGGCCAGAAGGUGUACCGAGACUGUAGCUGUAUCCCUCAGAAUCUUUCCUCUGGUUUUGGCCAUGCCACUGCAGGGAAAUGCACUUCAACUUGUCAGAGAAAGCCCCUCCUUCUGGUUUUCAUAUUCGUUGUAAUUUUCUUUACAUUCCUCAGCAGCAUUCCUGCACUAACGGCAACUCUACGAUGUGUCCGUGACCCUCAGAGAUCCUUUGCCCUGGGAAUCCAGUGGAUUGUAGUUAGAAUACUAGGGGGCAUCCCGGGGCCCAUCGCCUUCGGCUGGGUGAUCGACAAGGCCUGUCUGCUGUGGCAGGACCAGUGUGGCCAGCAGGGCUCCUGCUUGGUGUACCAGAAUUCGGCCAUGAGCCGCUACAUACUCAUCAUGGGGCUCCUGUACAAGGAAGAAGAGAAUGAAUUUAGAAGGCUGUAAACCCCAUCUGAGCCUUACACAUAGAUCUCCUUGAAUUGGAUUUUCACCAAGGCCGUGAUGGAUGUGGAGUCUCGGCUUUCUGACAACGUCUUCCAGAGCAGGCUUUCUCUAGAGGGUGGACUGCCUGUGUUCUCCUGGGAGAGAAUGCAUUUGCUUCCGAUGCCCAGGGCACGAAAGAGGUGGACGAAACAACGGAAGUGGAGGGGGUGGAUUCUCUACCUGGGAAACCCAGCAUGGCACACUCAUAUAGAAUUAAGAUCUUAUAAUAAGUGUGCAGAUGCGCCCGUUCUAAGGAAAUAAAGGGUUCUGCCCUCCUAAGAAUUCUGCCCUUGCAAGGGGUGUGAAACCUGCAGAGCUGCUUCCCGGCUUCUUCCUCCAGGAAGCCCUCCGUCCUCCUCCAAGCUGUAGACACAGGGCUGGUAAACAGGUAGCCAGGCGCCCCCACAGCCUCGGUGUGGAUCCAUGGCUGAGCAAGUCCUCCCUGGCCACUCCCAUCUCUGAUGACAGAACAUACCAUGAUGAGAGCCGCUGAAUUAGCAAGACAGUGUGGGGAAGGUACCCUCCGGGGACUGGGGGGCUUCUGGACUCCGAGAGCCCCUGCGUCCAUUCCUGUUUAUCGCGGCCACUUCCCAUCUGGGCAGGGCAAUCUCUGUACCUGGGGAGUGCAGCCGCCCAUGGAGACGGCUCAGAAUAAUGAGCUGAGUGUCUCCGUGUAGCUCCCGCCCCAGUGCGGAGCUCCUGGUACAGGAUGGCAGGUGGUGUCUAAAUAGCUAUUCAUAAGGACAUUAUCUCCAAGCACCGGGUGGAAACGAGCCUUCCUCCCCCCAGCUGAGAAGUGACAGGCACUUCCCUGUUUACUGAGGACAACAGUCAACCGCAGAGCGGCGUGGAGCUCGCAGUUCUUCUCAUGUCACAGUUGUGACUGAGUGUCAUGUCCUAAAGCUUCAGGAUGAAUGCAACUCCGCUCCACCAAGGGCCGGGGACAGAGUGAGAAGACACUGGCGCCAGGAGCGGGGAAGAGGGGAGGGGCCGGCAGCUGCCUAAAGAGCAGGCCCUCCUGCUGUUUCUGAGCCCCCGAGGGCCCUCUGACCCCAGACACCUUCCCUGCCAGCUGAACACCAUUCCAGAGUCAGAUCUUGGUUUUGUUUUCUUUCUUUUAAAAAUAUUUUAUUAUAAGGUGAAAAGAAAAGGAGAGUACACUAAGUCUUAGCCAUGGUUGGCCCUUUAGUCUGAAUUAGUAUAUCAGCUAUUUUACCAAGGGCAGGUUUGGACGGUGCAGAGACAGGAAGAGAGUAUCAGAGUGCCCAGCACCACAGAGAAGGGGUGGCUGGCCAGGGCGCCCAUUGCAGGCAGAUGAAAAGGGUGCCCCCGAACAGGCACGAUGGGUAGGGCACCCCCAAACAGGAGCAAUGGGAAGGGCACCCCCAAACAGGAGCAAUGGGAAAGGCACCCCCAAACAGGAGCAAUGGGAAAGGGCACCCCCAAACAGGCACAAUGGGAACGGCACCCCCAAACAGGCACGAUGGGAAGGGCACCCCCAAACAGGCACAAUGGGAAGGGCACCCCCAAACAGGAGCAAUGGGAAAGGGCACCCCCAAACAGGCACGAUGGGAAGGGCACCCCCAAACAGGAGCAAUGGGAAAGGGCACCCCCAAACAGGCACGAUGGGUGGGGCACCCCCAAACAGGAGCGAUGGAAAGGGCGCCCCCAAACAGGAGCGAUGGAAAGGGCACCCCCAAACAGGAGCGGGGGCCUCUGAAGGCAAGUGGCAGCAGCUUCCUAAUCCUGGCCCCACGUUGUUCCAAAGGUCCAUGAAGUUGACCAAACGCCACACAGCCACGGGAGACACAGUGGCCACCCUGGGGCGUCUACACUGAAGGCCAAGGGCAUGUGGAGGAAGAGCCAUCUGAGCCGAGGCCCGGGGAGGAGCCAGCAGGCCAAGGAGGCGGAAGAAACCACGCAGUGGCGUCCAGGGCAGGGCAGGUGCGUCAUCCGGGCGGGAUGCAGAGACACGUCCUUCCACCAACCAUCUGAGGAGCACUUGGCACCCACACAAUGAGCCCGGCAAGGGCCACGCCAGGAGGCAGCGCACGGGGCAGAGCCUCUGAGCCAGAGAGGGGGAGGUCCCUUGGGAGGCCCCUGCCAUCCCCCGCUCUGGGUGGGCCUCUCCAGCCAGACUCUGCGCCCCAAGGGCAGGGCUGGGCCUAAGCCACACCUCGGGGUGCACGGGCUGUGGGGGGCCGCUCCUGGACACGGAAGGACGACACCGGCUUCCCUGUACCUCUGCUGGGGCCGCGGGUCCCAUGUCGUCAGCGUGGCCACUAGGCUGCCAGCCUAGCACAGCCUCCAGGGCAGCCAUGGCCCAACCUGCCUUCCGAGCCUCAGGGGUAUCCCUGAGCACAUGGGAGUGCAGGAAAAGGUACCCCAGGGGAUCCCCACUCACCUCCCGGCCAUGUCCUACCAGGCACUAGUGCCGCGCUGCAGCCACCCCCGGGCCUUACCCACCCCCACCAGCUUCAUUGCCUUCCAGGUCCCAGCACCACCAGUUUCAUUGCUUUCCAGGUCCCAGCACCACCAGCUUCAUUGCUUUCCAGGUCCCAGCACCACCAACUUCAUUGCCUUCCAGGCUCUCAGCAGCAUAAGAGACCUACACACACACACACGUGCACACAUACAUAGAAGGGGCUGACUCACACGCCACCCCAUAUGCAAGCCGCAGAAGCUGGGCGUCCACUGAGCAGCAGAGAUAGCCCAUCCCAGAGGGCAAGGAGGAUCCCUGGGGUCCCUACGAGAACACCUCGCCCAGGUCCUGCCCGCGGCCCCCCACGAGGCCUCUUUGGGAGGGAGGCUGCCCCCUACACCACUCAGUGCUAGGACUUACCCAUGCACCCCCCAGCCCUGUGCAACCCUGCCCGUGCACCAAUGACCCCACUCACCCCUGACCCUGCUCACCCCAACCCCGCUCACCUGUAGCCCCACCAGGUUCUUAAGCAAAAGCUCAGUCUGUGUGCACACAGCAAACACAAUUCUGCCUAUAUUUUCUCGGGGUUUGGGGCUCACAUUGGACACUGGAGGCUCUCUUGAGUGAGUAAGAGCAGCAGCUCAGGCUUUUGAAGGCAAAAUGGAAUGGACGCAGGGCCCAGGAGACACCAACUGGGUGAGAGCAGGGCUCCAGAGCCAGCAGAUGGCUGGGGUGGGGGAUGCAUGCCCCCUGCCACCCACUCCAGCAAACCCGGUCCCCUGACUUGGGUUGUGUCCAGCAAUGGCUUUCUGGGCUUGAAGGCAGAGCUGCCAGGAGGAAGGAGUCCCUCUGCAAUGUCAGAAGCACCAAACACAGGGGAGACCUAACUUUCAGGGCCUGGGGGAAGCUGGGGUGGCCAGGCUGGUGGGAAGGAGACAUUAACAUUUUCCGAGAAGCCCUUUAAUUCUUCCCAAUAAACCGAACGAGUACAAGCCUCAGCAUGGAAGCACAGCUUUCUAGAAGCUGGAAAAUCAGGCUCAUCACAAAAGCUCGAGCACAGUUAAUUUCCUCUGACAUUUCCUCCUGUGGUUAGUCUUGGAGCCAGCAGGUGGCCGGAGGCGCCCCAUUCUUUCCCAUAAAUGGACGGUCUCUAAGGAAUCAAGUCAGGCCCUCAUCUCCAAACCCUCAUCCCAUUUUUCCCUGGCCUGCACGUGGCCAGCUGUGCCCCGCGCCUCGUAGGCCUGUCCCUGGCUGUGCCCCGCGCCUCAUAGGCUUGUCCCUGGCUGUGCCCCGUGCCUCGCAGGCCUGUCCCUGGCCGGCUGUGUCCCGUUCCUCGCAGGCCUGUCCCCGGCUGUGCCCCGUGCCUCGCAGGCCUGUCCCCGGCUGUGCCCCGUGCCUCGCAGGCCUGUCUCUUGGGCAGAGUGGCUCCCUCUCUCCAUCAGUCCUUCCUCCAUCACACCGGUGCUCGUGCAGAAGCCAGGGCUCGCAGACAUCACCCUAGGCACUGAGGAUACCAGCUGCCCGAACGGACAGACGGACAGAUGCUCAGCCUCCUCAGGUGCUGGCCCAUGGCCUCCCAGGCUGGAUGAGCAGCAGGUCCCUACGGGGGACGUGGCAGAGGGGACCCCAGCCCCAGCAGGGCCCAGCGAGCCGGGUGCCCAGCACAGCACUCACCUGAGCAGCUGUCUCCACCCCGCAUUGAGCCCCUCCUGGGGACCGCCCCUUUCCAAAGACGCCCUGGUCAUCUUAGACCCCCAGACCCUCCGGAAGGCGACCGCCAUGCCUUAAUAACUUGCGGGGGCUCAGGCAGAGCUGUAGGGAUCCUGCCAAGCUGCCCGAUUCCUUGUGUUCCUGGCAGGGGGAUCCACAUCAUCCUCACCCCACUCCAUGUGUGGGACGGGGCACCCAGGAAUGUCUGGGGCCGAGGAAGGGGGUGGACCUGAGGGAACCCCUACCUGCAGAAAUAAUCAUGAAAGGGGUGGAGCAGAUGCGGGGGACCCGCGUCCCCACCCUCACCCCCAGGGGCUGAGUCGACGCCUGCAGCCAGCGCCUGCACUCCUGUUCACAUGGGCUUCCCUGGCCUCUGUGCCUGCUUUGCGCCUGCGCGGCAGGUGAACGACCCCAGCCCCCUUGCCUGGUGAGUGGGCCUGUCUGCCGUGGAUUCCCCAGCUGCAUGGUGCCUCGGGUGCCCGCGAUGGUCCUGGCCCCCUCCCUCGCAUCGGCCACCUCUCUGCUCCAGCGGUGCUUCCUGUGUGUCCUCCCAGUAAACCUCCUGCCCCUGACCCCAGUCUCCCCUCUGUCUCAGGGGCCCACAGGGAGACAGACAACCUCUGGGUGUCCGACGUCUCAUCAAGUCCUUUGAUACUCCAGGGGAGUGGGGUUGACAGUUUUCCAUGGGAGGACGGAGCUCAACAGAGGGUGUCACCUGCACAAGGUCACCAUAGGCUCUGACCCUGCAGCCAAGGAAGGCUCUGCAGGAGCCCCGGGAAUCCCAGCCACAGAACAGGAGGGAGCUGCAUGCUCUCACUCCACGCCCGCCCUCCACCGAGCCGCAGGCCAGAGCCCUGGCUGUGCUAUUACUCACUAUUAUCUCAGAUUUACCAUUCAUUUUACCAGGAGAGAAACUGCAAAAGGAAAUUAACAUUUCCAUACUCUGCAGCGAGAUACUUUCAUGGACGCAUUCUGAGAUUUAUUCUUUAAUAAUGGAAAGGAAACACCCUACUGGCUUCCAAUUCGGGGCCUGACAGUUCAUCCUAUUCCAGGCAGAGAACCGCAAUUCAAUAAACGCGCUUUCAUUUGUUUUGUUUUA